CCUUGAGCAGGCUAAGGCUUCCCUUUUAAUUAAAGAGCUGCACUCCAGCUCUCCAGUCAUAAAAGGACAGCAGCCAACCGCUGUGGGCUGAAUUUGGGGCUGCCUUUGAGUCAGCCUGAGCUGAUGUGUUUUCUGGAAUGACUUUUUCUUUUUUGAAGUCGAUCUACAGGAAUCGGCCUCAUCAGCUGUGUGUGUUGAGAGGUGGGGACGGGGGAGGGAUGUGUCAGACUCUGAGCGUGGACCAGAACUGCGCUCGGAGACUUUCAGUGAAAGCAGAGGAGAGAUUUCCAAAGGUUGUAUUUUCCUUCUGGUUGGAGCCUCUCAUCCACAUUGUGGUUGCUUUCAGCUAUGUAACGUUUUUCGAUCCCAUGAGAUGGAAAUCGACCAGUGCUUGCUAGAGUCCCUUCCCCUUGGCCAACGGCAGCGUCUAGUGAAGCGCAUGCGCUGUGAGCAAAUCAAAGCCUACUAUGAGCGCGAGAAGGCUUUUCAGAAGCAGGAAGGGUUCCUGAAAAGGCUGAAGCAUGCGAAGAAUCCGAAAGUUCACUUCAACCUCACGGACAUGCUACAGGACGCGAUUAUCCACCACAAUGACAAAGAAGUGCUUCGGCUCCUGAAGGAGGGGGCAGACCCCCACACCCUCGUCUCCUCGGGAGGGUCCCUGCUCCAUCUGUGUGCUCGGUAUGAUAAUGCCUUCAUUGCAGAAAUUCUGAUUGACAGAGGAGUCAACGUCAACCACCAGGAUGAAGACUUCUGGACGCCCAUGCACAUUGCCUGUGCCUGCGAUAACCCUGAUAUUGUCCUGCUUCUUGUAUUAGCUGGAGCCAAUGUCCUUCUCCAGGAUGUGAAUGGAAAUAUCCCAUUAGAUUAUGCUGUAGAAGGGACAGAAUCCAGCUCUAUCCUGUUGACCUAUCUGGAUGAAAAUGGAGUGGAUUUGACCUCACUGCGCCAGAUGAAGCUUCAGAGACCAAUGAGUAUGUUAACAGAUGUCAAACACUUCUUAUCAUCUGGAGGAAAUGUCAAUGAGAAAAACGAUGAAGGAGUAACCCUGUUACACAUGGCGUGUGCGAGUGGCUACAAGGAGGUGGUGUCUCUUAUCCUGGAACAUGGUGGAGACCUCAACAUAGUAGAUGAUCAGUACUGGACUCCCCUCCACUUGGCAGCCAAAUAUGGCCAGACAAAUCUGGUGAAACUUCUCCUGAUGCAUCAGGCAAACCCACACCUCGUGAACUGUAAUGAGGAGAAGGCGUCAGAUAUUGCUGCCUCUGAGUUUAUUGAGGAAAUGCUGCUGAAAGCCGAAAUUGCCUGGGAAGAAAAAAUGAAAGAGCCUUUAUCUGCUUCUACCUUAGCUCAAGAAGAGCCCUAUGAAGAGAUCAUUCACGAUCUUCCCGUACUGUCGAGUAAGCUCAGUCCCCUGGUGUUACCAAUUGCCAAGCAAGACAGUUUGUUGGAAAAAGACAUUAUGUUCAAAGAUGCAACAAAAGGUCUGUGUAAGCAGCAGUCUCAGGACAGCAUCCCUGAAAACCCCAUGAUGAGCGGUUCCACCAAACCCGAGCAGGUCAAGCUAAUGCCUCCUGCCCCAAACGAUGACCUGGCAACGCUCAGCGAGCUCAAUGAUGGCAGCCUGCUCUAUGAGAUUCAGAAGCGCUUUGGGAACAAUCAGAUCUAUACAUUCAUUGGAGACAUUCUUUUGCUUGUUAACCCAUACAAGGAGCUUCCAAUUUAUUCUUCCAUGGUGUCCCAGCUGUAUUUCAGCUCCUCAGGGAAGCUGUGUUCCUCGCUGCCUCCUCACCUCUUCUCCUGUGUGGAGAGAGCCUUUCACCAGCUCUUCCGGGAACAGCGGCCUCAGUGUUUCAUCCUCAGUGGAGAAAGGGGAUCAGGAAAGUCUGAAGCCAGCAAACAAAUCAUAAGACACCUCACCUGCAGGGCUGGCGCCAGCAGGGCCACACUGGAUUCCAGAUUCAAACAUGUCGUGUGCAUCUUAGAAGCCUUUGGACAUGCCAAGACCACACUUAAUGAUUUGUCCAGUUGCUUCAUCAAGUAUUUUGAACUGCAGUUCUGUGAGAGGAAACAACAGCUAACCGGAGCCAGAAUUUAUACAUAUUUGCUAGAGAAAUCCAGACUUGUUUCACAACCUCUUGGCCAGAGCAAUUUUCUCAUUUUCUACUUGUUGAUGGAUGGGUUAUCUGCUGAAGAAAAAUAUGGACUUCAUCUUAAUAAUUUAUGUGCACACCGGUAUUUGAACCAGACCAUACAGGAUGAUGCAUCCACAGGGGAGCGUUCUCUGAACAGGGAGAAAUUGGCUGUUUUGAAACGAGCCCUGAAUGUAGUUGGCUUCAGCAGCUUGGAGGUGGAGAAUCUGUUCGUAAUUCUAGCAGCAAUAUUGCACCUUGGAGACAUUCGGUUUACUGCCCUGAAUGAGGGGAACUCCGCCUUCGUUUCUGACCUCCAGCUCCUGGAACAAGUGGCUGGAAUGUUACAAGUAUCAACAGAUGAAUUGGCAUCUGCCUUAACAACUGAUAUUCAAUAUUUUAAAGGGGAUAUGAUAAUACGACGACAUACCAUACAGAUUGCUGAGUUUUUCCGAGACCUCUUGGCCAAGUCCCUGUACAGUCGUUUGUUUAGCUUUUUGGUGAAUACCAUGAAUUCUUGCCUCCACAGUCAAGAUGAACAGAAAAGCAUGCAGACAUUGGAUAUUGGAAUAUUGGACAUUUUUGGUUUUGAAGAGUUUCAAAAGAAUGAAUUUGAACAACUUUGUGUCAACAUGACCAAUGAGAAGAUGCACCACUAUAUCAAUGAAGUGCUUUUUCUCCACGAGCAAGUGGAAUGUGUACAAGAGGGAGUUACCAUGGAAACAGCAUAUUCUCCUGGUAACCAGAAUGGAGUUUUGGACUUUUUUUUCCAGAAGCCAUCUGGAUUUCUCACCUUAUUGGAUGAAGAAAGUCAAAUGAUUUGGUCAGUGGAAUCAAAUUUUCCAAAAAAACUACAAAGUCUCCUAGAAUCCUCAAACACAAAUGCGGUGUACUCCCCCAUGAAGGAUGGGAAUGGGAAUGUUGCCCUCAAAGACCACGGUACAGCCUUCACCAUCAUGCACUACGCAGGAAGGGUAAUGUAUGAUGUUGUUGGGGCGAUUGAAAAAAAUAAAGACUCCCUUUCACAGAAUCUUCUAUUUGUAAUGAAAACUAGUGAAAAUGUCGUGAUCAAUCAUUUGUUCCAGUCGAAAUUGUCACAAACAGGAUCCCUCGUAUCUGCCUAUCCUUCCUUUAAAUUCCGAGGACAUAAGUCUGCCCUGCUCAGUAAGAAAAUGACAGCUUCUUCAAUUAUUGGAGAAAACAAGAAUUAUCUAGAACUUAGUAAGUUAUUAAAAAAGAAAGGAACUUCUACAUUUCUUCAAAGAUUGGAACGAGGAGAUCCAGUCACCAUAGCAUCACAACUCAGGAAAUCACUAAUGGAUAUUAUUGGAAAACUUCAGAAGUGCACUCCACACUUCAUUCAUUGCAUCAGGCCCAAUAACUCAAAGCUGCCAGAUACUUUUGAUAAUUUUUACGUGUCUGCUCAGCUACAAUAUAUUGGGGUCCUGGAGAUGGUGAAGAUCUUCCGAUAUGGAUACCCUGUUCGCCUUUCCUUCUCGGAUUUCCUGUCAAGGUAUAAGCCACUGGCUGAUACAUUCCUGCGUGAGAAGAAGGAACAGUCAGCUGCCGAGCGAUGUCGACUUGUUCUCCAGCAGUGUAAAUUACAAGGCUGGCAGAUGGGAGUCCGAAAAGUGUUUCUAAAAUACUGGCAUGCUGACCAACUCAAUGAUUUGUGCCUACAGUUGCAGAGAAAAAUUAUAACCUGCCAAAAAGUUAUCAGAGGAUUUUUAGCACGCCAGCACCUGCUUCAGAGAAUAAGCAUCAGACAACAAGAGGUGACUUCUAUCAAUAGCUUUCUGCAGAACACAGAGGACAUGGGGCUGAAAACCUACGAUGCCCUGGUCAUUCAGAAUGCUUCAGACAUUGCCCGGGAAAAUGACCGGCUCCGUAGUGAAAUGAACGCUCCCUACCAUAAAGAGAAGUUAGAGGUCAGGAACAUGCAAGAGGAAGGAAGCAAAAGAACCGAUGACAAGAGUGGACCCAGGCAUUUCCACCCCAGCUCCAUGUCAGUCUGCGCGGCCGUGGAUGGCCUGGGCCAGUGCCUCGUUGGCCCGUCCAUCUGGUCUCCUUCGCUGCACUCGGUGUUCAGCAUGGAUGACAGCAGCAGCCUCCCGUCUCCACGGAAACAGCCCCCGCCCAAGCCAAAGAGGGACCCCAACACCCGGCUGAGUGCUUCCUAUGAGGCUGUGAGCGCCUGCCUCUCCGCGGCCAGGGAAGCGGCCAACGAAGCUCUGGCCCGGCCCAGACCGCACAGCGACGACUACAGCACCAUGAAGAAGAUUCCUCCUCGAAAGCCCAAGCGCAGCCCCAACACCAAGCUCAGCGGCUCCUACGAGGAGAUAUCGGGGUCCCGGCCCGGGGACGCGAGGCCCGCGGGCGCCCCGGGGGCAGCAGCGCGCGUUCUGACCCCCGGGACUCCGCAGUGCGCGCUGCCCCCGGCGGCGCCUCCGGGUGACGAGGACGACAGCGAGCCUGUGUACAUCGAGAUGCUGGGGCACGCGGCCAGGCCCGAUAGCCCGGACCCCGGGGAGUCCGUGUACGAGGAGAUGAAGUGUUGCCUGCCCGACGACGGCGGCCCGGGCGCGGGCUCCUUCCUGCUCCACGGCGCAUCGCCGCCCCUGCUCCACCGCGCGCCGGAGGACGAGGCGGCGGGGCCCCCAGGGGACGCGUGCGACAUCCCGCCGCCCUUCCCCAACCUGCUGCCGCACCGGCCGCCCCUGCUGGUGUUCCCCCCGACCCCCGUCACCUGCUCCCCCGCCUCCGACGAGUCGCCCCUGACACCCCUGGAGGUGAAGAAGCUGCCAGUCCUGGAGACCAACCUCAAGUACCCCGUGCAGCCGGAGGGGUCGAGCCCGCUGUCCCCGCAGUACUCCAAGAGCCAGAAGGGCGACGGCGACAGGCCCGCGUCCCCCGGCCUGGCGCUGUUCAACGGGUCCGGCCGAGCCUCCCCGCCGUCCACGCCGCCCCCGCCCCCGCCCCCGCCCGGGCCGCCCCCCGCGCCCUACAGGCCCUGCGCGCACUUGGCCUUCCCGCCGGAGCCCGCCCCGGUGAACGCGGGGAAAGCGGGGCCGAGCGCAGAGGCGCCCAAGGUUCACCCAAAGCCAAACUCUGCCCCCGUGGCCGGGCCCUGCAGCUCCUUCCCCAAGAUCCCAUAUUCCCCCGUGAAGGCCACCAGGGCGGACGCCAGGAAGGCCGGCUCCAGUGCCUCGCCCCCCGCGCCCUACAGCCCUCCCAGCUCCAGGCCUCUCAGCAGCCCCCUGGACGAGCUCGCCAGCCUCUUCAACUCGGGGAGGAGUGUGCUUCGGAAAUCCGCGGCGGGAAGAAAAAUCAGGGAAGCAGAAGGUUUUGAAACUAACAUGAACAUAAGUAGCCGAGAUGACCCUAGUACGUCAGAAAUUACUUCCGAGACUCAAGACAGAAAUGCAAAUAACCAUGGAAUUCAGUUAUCUAAUUCACUAUCUAGUGCUAUAACUGCUGAAAAUGGAAAUUCCAUCUCAAAUGGUUUACCUGAAGAAGAUGGAUACUCACGGUUGUCUAUAAGUGGCACAGGGACUUCGACAUUUCAAAGACACAGGGACAGUCACACCACUCAGGUAAUCCAUCAGCUGAGGCUCUCAGAGAAUGAAAGUGUGGCCCUGCAGGAACUCUUGGACUGGAGGAGAAAGCUCUGUGAGGAAGGACAAGACUGGCAGCAGAUCCUGCACCACGCUGAGCCCAGGGUGCCUCCCCCACCACCUUGCAAGAAGCCCAGCCUUCUGAAGAAGCCGGAAGGGGCCUCCUGCAACAGGCUGCCGUCUGAGCUCUGGGACACCACCAUUUGAUGUGGCCUGAACUGCAGACUUACAAAAUAGAACUGCCUACUGAUUCCGGGCUGCAACAACAGAAGGCUGCCUUCUGACAUGCGCUGGGGCUUCUCUCCACGCAUUUAGACAAAAAAAGCACAGGACACAGACACUAAAUAUAUGAGAUCCCGUGUGUGUGUGUGUGUGUUUGUGUGUGUGUGUGUGGGUUCUUUCUUAUCCAUCUCGUGGUGAUACACUCUGAUUUUCAAGCUCCUCAUUUACGGCUCUGUGCUACCCCUAGGUAGCAAGAGAGAGGCUGGGAAAAGUGUGGACGUGGCCAGAGCGAGAGAGUAGCGGAGGAAAGGAGCAAUCCAUGCACACUCUGUACAGUUGUUUUUCUACGGUUCAACAGUCUGUUUAUUGUACUUCCAAUGGUUUUAUUAUAAUACAGUAUACGGGACAUAUAUUUUAUUUCUUUGUAGCUACUUGUGUUUUAUUGGUAUUAUAAACCUGAUAAUUAUUUACAUGUUUAUUACUGUAAUUUUAUAAAUUUAUGCAAUUGGUGGUGCUUCCUUUCUUCAAAAUACAGAUUUUAAAAAAUCAUUUCUAGAUUAUUUUUUUCCUCCACAGUCCUUUUUUUUCACCUAACGCACCUAAAUCUUGAAACUACAUUGUUGUUUUAGCUUCGCCAGUGUCACCCCUUGCAAAACUAUGAAUUGAGCCCCAUGUUUUAGGUGUUACUCAUGGAUGAGGAGGCUGUUCUUUCCUAUGCCCUGUAUUUCUGGAUAAGUGGAUUGUGUACCCUUUAGUUAAAUUUCACCUCCCGACUUCAGCAUAGAUCACAGGAAAUCACAUGGCACACGGUUAAACACGUAUGGCUUCAAAUCCAUAGCCGGUGGUGUAAAAUGAUCAUAUUCAUUCAAAGGCCUACACAGUACAAAUGAGCACGCUGCCAUGUACUGGUUUGAGCAGUAGGGGCUGCAUCGCACAGCGCUCGUCCCCCGGGACUUACACUGCAUGAUUCCCUCACUGUAUAUCCUCAACCCUCCCAUAAUGCAAGGCCUUGUUCAUUGAUGUGCUUUCGUCGGCUGUCGGAAAGUUCUGAGCAGUGGCUCCAGACCACCUUGUCUUGCUACUUGGAACUUUUUAUUCAUACCAGCCUUUGAAAAGUUACUGUGCCAAUAAAGAGGUACAACUGUGUUCUUCUA